GUUGUUUGCAGAGAGGCCGUGGCUACAAAAUGGAAGUGCUUUUGCGACCUGGGCUCCAUUUUAGGAAUUCUUGCCCGAUUUUAACCACUUGAACGCGGAAGUGGCUUUCCUAUUCUCUUCCAAGCCAGCCUUUAAUUUUAAACGCUGUAAUUAACAGUUCACAGGGGUCAAAUUCCUUUAUUCCGGAACAUUCCACUUUGAGAGGGAUCUGUCCUCUUUGGUCCCCUGCGUUUUCAAAUAUUUGAGGAAAGGUGUCGCCUCUUUUUCUGUGGAAAGAGGAAGCUCAUGAGCGCGAAACAGCAGGGGACGGAGGGCGAGAAGGGCUUUCUCAGGUUGCGGGUCGGAGGGCAGAAGCACAGUUCCCAGUACAGAGACCCGGACAGGUGGCUGUUUCUCACGCUCACUUUGGAUUGCUCCCUACGGCUUCCUCCGCAGCCAUGUCUGACAAACCUGGUAUGGCUGAGAUCGAGAAAUUCGAUAAGUCGAAACUGAAGAAGACAGAAACGCAAGAGAAGAAUCCAUUGUCUUCCAAAGAAACUAUCGAACAGGAGAGGCAAGCAGGCGAAUCUUAAACAGGCAUGUGCCACCAAUAUCUACUGUACAUUCUACAAGCAUUGCUUUCUUAUUUUACUUCUUUUACUUGUUUAACUUGGUUAGAUGCAAACACGUUGGAUGAGUUUGAAAGGACUAUGCUGCCCUUUUGACAUCAAAGACCUGCUGACAAUGGAGGCCACGCCUGCUUCUCCCAUCGCCUGUCUGGCUGGCAGGGAAGGAAAAUAGCUUGAAUGUUGGUGAAAGACUUAGCGGAGUGGGAGGGCAGUGAAAUCUAGAGUAAAACCAAGUUGGGCCAAGUGUCCUGCAGAAUCUAAAAUGAAGUUUAAUCAGCGUGCCAUUUUUGUUGUUGUUUGAAAGAUUUUAAUUUUUGGAAUGCACAGUUUUUAUUUAAAAAAGACAUUUUUAAACCACUGCUUGUGAGAUUGCUUGUUGAUUGGAAAGAGUGUUUUAUUCACCAUUUAAACGUUUGCAAAGUGGCGUGCCCCUUGGCCUCACAGGCAAAGAAUAACUUAAAAGCUGACGAUUUGAAUAAAUUAUGUUACAGUAUGAAAUAUGUUUUACCUGGAUAUGUAAAAUACCUUCUUUAUUCUAGCUAAUUGGGAGAUGAUUUUUUUUGGCUAAUUGAGAUUACCUUUAGAUUAUGUUUUCAAAACUGGCUUAUACUGUAAUCUACAACUAAUAAGCACUAAUUUAGAGUUCAGCUAUAUUGUUGCAUGUAGUGAGAAGGGACUUAAUUACAAACUUAAGACGUAAGUGUGCAAUAAAGUAAGCUAAGAAGAAAA